GCACUGCAGCGCCAACGUCCGAGCGGGCGGCCGAGCUCCCGGAGCGGCCUGGCCCCGAGCCCCGAGCGGGCGUCGCUCAGCAGCAGGUCGCGGCCGCAGCCCCAUCCAGCCCCGCGCCCGCCAUGCCGUCCGCCGGCCCCGCCUGAGCCGCGGCCUCCGCGCGCGGGCGGGCCUGGGGACGGCGGGGCCAUGCGCGCGCUGCCCUAACGAUGCCGCCCGCCGCGCCCGCCCGCCUGGCGCUGGCCCUGGGCCUGGGCCUGUGGCUCGGGGCGCUGGCGGGGGGCCCCGGGCGCGGCUGCGGGCCUUGCGAGCCCCCCUGCCUCUGCGGCCUAGCGCCCGGCGCCGCCUGCCGCGUCAACUGCUCGGGCCGCGGGCCGCGGGUGCGGACGCUCGGUCCCGCGCUGCGCAUCCCCGCGGACGCCACAGCGCUAGACGUCUCCCACAACCUGCUCCGGGCGCUGGACGUUGGGCUCCUGGCGAACCUCUCGGCGCUGGCAGAGCUGGAUAUAAGCAACAACAAGAUUUCUACGUUAGAAGAAGGAAUAUUUGCUAAUUUAUUUAAUUUAAGUGAAAUAAACCUGAGUGGGAACCCGUUUGAGUGUGACUGUGGCCUGGCGUGGCUGCCGCGAUGGGCGGAGGAGCAGCAGGUGCGGGUGGUGCAGCCCGAGGCAGCCACGUGUGCUGGGCCUGGCUCCCUGGCUGGCCAGCCUCUGCUUGGCAUCCCCUUGCUGGACAGUGGCUGUGGUGAGGAGUAUGUCGCCUGCCUCCCUGACAACAGCUCAGGCACCGUGGCAGCAGUGUCCUUUUCAGCUGCCCACGAAGGCCUGCUUCAGCCAGAGGCCUGCAGCGCCUUCUGCUUCUCCACCGGCCAGGGCCUCGCAGCCCUCUCGGAGCAGGGCUGGUGCCUGUGUGGGGCGGCCCAGCCCUCCAGUGCCUCCUUCGCCUGCCUGUCCCUCUGCUCCGGCCCCCUGCCGCCUCCUGCCCCCACCUGUAGGAGCCCCACCCUCCUCCAGCACGUCUUCCCUGCCUCCCCAGGGGCCGCCCUGGUGGGGCCCCACGGACCCCUGGCCUCCGGCCAGCUAGCAGCCUUCCACAUCGCUGCCCCGCUCCCUGUCACUGCCACACGCUGGGACUUUGGAGACGGCUCCCCCGAGGUGGAUGCCGCUGGGCCGGCUGCCUCGCAUCGCUAUGUGCUGCCUGGGCGCUAUCACGUGACGGCCGUGCUGGCCCUGGGGACCGGCUCAGCCCUGCUGGGGACAGACGUGCAGGUGGAAGCGGCACCUGCCGCCCUGGAGCUCGUGUGCCCGUCCUCGGUGCAGAGUGACGAGAGCCUCGACCUCAGCAUCCAGAACCGCGGUGGUUCAGGCCUGGAGGCCGCCUACAGCAUCGUGGCCCUGGGCGAGGAGCCGGCCCGAGCGGUGCACCCGCUCUGCCCCUCGGACACGGAGAUCUUCUCUGGCAAUGGGCACUGCUACCGCCUGGUGGUGGAGAAGGCGGCCUGGCUGCAGGCGCAGGAGCAGUGUCGGGCCUGGGCCGGGGCCACCCUGGCAAUGGUGGACAGUCCCGCCGUGCAGCGCUUCCUGGUCUCCCGGGUCACCAGGAGCCUAGACAUGUGGAUCGGCUUCUCGACUGUGCAGGGGGUGGAGGUGGGCCCAGCGCCGCAGGGCGAGGCCUUCAGCCUGGAGAGCUGCCAGAACUGGCUGCCCGGGGAGCCACACCCAGCCACAGCUGAGCACUGCGUCCGGCUCGGGCCCACCGGGUGGUGUAACACCGACCUGUGCUCAGCGCCGCACAGCUACGUCUGCGAGCUGCGGCCUGGAGGCCCAGUGCAGGAUGCCGAGAACCUCCUCGUGGGAGCGCCCAGUGGGGACCUGUAGGGACCCCUGAUGCCUCUGGCACGGCAGUACGGCCUCUCAGCCCCGCACGAGCCCCUGGAGGUCAUGGUAUUCCCGGGCCUGCGUCUGAGCCGUGAAGCCUUCCUCACCACGGCCGAAUUUGGGACCCAGGAGCUCCGGCGGCCCGCCCAGCUGCGGCUGCAGGUGUACCGGCUCCUCAGCACAGCAGGGACCCCGGAGAACGGCAGCGAGCCUGAGAGCAGGUCCCCGGACAACAGGACCCAGCUGGUCCCCGCGUGCAUGCCAGGGGGACGCUGGUGCCCUGGAGCCAACAUCUGCUUGCCGCUGGACGCCUCCUGCCACCCCCAGGCCUGCGCCAAUGGCUGCACGUCAGGGCCAGGGCUACUCGGGUCCCCCUAUGCGCUAUGGAGAGAGUUCCUCUUCUCCGUUCCCGCGGGGCCCCCCGCGCAGUACUCGGUCACCCUCCACGGCCAGGAUGUCCUCAUGCUCCCUGGUGACCUCGUUGGCUUGCAGCACGACGCUGGCCCUGGCGCCCUCCCGCACUGCUCGCCGGCUCCCGGCCACCCUGGUCCCCAGGCCCCGUACCUCUCCGCCAACGCCUCGUCAUGGCUGCCCCACUUGCCAGCCCAGCUGGAGGGCACUUGGGCCUGCCCUGCCUGUGCCCUGCGGCUGCUUGCAGCCACGGAACAGCUCACCGUGCUGCUGGGCCUGAGGCCCAACCCUGGGCUGCGGCUGCCUGGGCGCUAUGAGGUCCGGGCAGAGGUGGGCAAUGGCGUGUCCAGGCACAACCUGUCCUGCAGCUUUGACGUGGUCUCCUCAGUGGCUGGGCUGCGGGUCAUCUACCCUGCCCCCCGCGACGGCCGCCUCUACGUGCCCACCAACGGCUCAGCCUCGGUGCUCCAGGUGGACUCUGGUGCCAGCGCCACGGCCACGGCUUGCUGGCCUGGGGGCAGUGUCAGCGCCCGCUUUGAGAAUGCCUGCCCUGCCCUGGUGGCCACCUUCGUGCCCGGCUGCCCCUGGGAGACCAAUGAUACCCUGUUCUCAGUGGUAGCACUGCCGUGGCUCGGUGAGGGGGAGCACGUGAUGGACGUUGUGGUGGAAAACAGCGCCAGCCGGGCCAACCUCAGCCUGCGGGUGACGGCGGAGGAGCCCAUCUGUGGCCUCCGCGCCACGCCCAGCCCCGAGGCCCGUGUACUGCAGGGAGUCCCAGUGAGGUACAGCCCCGUGGUGGAGGCCGGCUCGGACAUGGUCUUCUGGUGGACCAUCAACGACAAGCAGUCCCUGACCUUCCAGAACGUGGUCUUCAAUGUCAUUUAUCAGAGCGCGGCGGUCUUCAAGCUCUCACUGACGGCCUCCAACCACGUGAGCAACGUCACCGUGAACUACAACAUCACCGUGGAGCGGAUGAACAGGAUGCAGGGCCUGCGGGUCUCUACAGUGCCAGCCGUGCUGUCCCCCAAUGCCACGCUGGCACUGACGGCGGGCGUGCUGGUGGACUCGGCCGUGGAGGUGGCCUUCCUGUGGACCUUUGGGGAUGGGGAGCAGGCCCUCCACCAGUUCCAGCCUCCAUACAACGAGUCCUUCCCGGUUCCAGACCCCUCGGUGGCCCAGGUGCUGGUGGAGCACAAUGUCACCCACACCUACGCUGCCCCAGGUGAGGAUGAGGGGGUGAGGGGCCACUGCCUUUCAGGCUCUGAGCACGGGGCCCCCUUCCUCCCCCAGCCCUCACUGUGACCUCACCUGGGCUGAUGGCUUAGCCCUACUGGGGUGAGGGAGGGGCCAGGCGUGGGAGGAGUGGACAGGCGUGAGUACUGGGAGGGGGUGCUGAUCCGCAGUGGCCGGGUGCCCAUUGUGUCCUUGGAGUGUGUGUCCUGCAAGGCACAGGCCGUGUACGAAGUGAGCCGCAGCUCCUACGUGUACCUGGAGGGCCGCUGCCUCAAUUGCAGCAGCGGCUCCAAGCGAGGGCGGUGGGCUGCACGUACGUUCAGCAACAAGACGCUGGUGCUGGAUGAGACCACCACAUCCACGGGCAGCGCAGGCAUGUGACUGGUGCUGCGGCGGGGCGUGCUGCGGGACGGCGAGGGAUACACCUUCACGCUGACGGUGCUGGGCCGCUCUGGCGAGGAGGAGGGCUGCGCCUCCAUCCCCCUGUCCCCCAACCGCCCGCCGCUGGGGGGCUCUUGCCGCCUCUUCCCACUGGGCGCUGUGCACGCUCUCACCACCAAGGUGCACUUCGAAUGCAUGGGCUGGCAUGACGCGGAGGAUGCUGGCGCCCCGCUGGUGUACGCCCUGCUGCUGCAGCGCUGCCGCCAGGGCCACUGCGAGGAGUUCUGUGUCUACAAGGGCAGCCUCUCCGGCUACGGAGCCGUGCUGCCCCCGGGUUUCAGGCCACACUUCGAGGUGGGCCUGGCCGUGGUGGUGCAGGACCAGCUGGGAGCCGCUGUGGUCGCCCUCAACAGGUCUCUGGCCAUCACCCUCCCAGAGCCCAACGGCAGCGCAAUGGGGCUCACAGUCUGGCUGCACGGGCUCACCGCUAGUGUGCUCCCAGGGCUGCUGCGGCAGGCCGAUCCCCAGCACGUCAUCGAGUACUCGCUGGCCCUGGUCACUGUGCUGAACGAGUACGAGCGGGCCCUGGACGUGGCGGCAGAGCCCAAGCACGAGCGGCAGCGCCGAGCCCAGAUACGCAAGAACAUCACGGAGACUCUGGUGUCCCUGAGGGUCCACACUGUGGAUGACAUCCAGCAGAUCGCUGCUGCGCUGGCCCAGUGCAUGGGGCCCAGCAGGGAGCUCGUAUGCCGCUCGUGCCUGAAGCAGACGCUGCACAAGCUGGAGGCCAUGAUGCGCAUCCUGCAGGCAGAGACCACCGCGGGCACCGUGACGCCCACCGCCAUCGGAGACAGCAUCCUCAACAUCACAGGAGACCUCAUCCACCUGGCCAGCUCAGACGUGCGGGCACCACAGCGCUCAGAGCUGGGAGCCGAGUCACCAUCGCGGAUGGUGGCGUCCCAGGCCUACAACCUGACCUCUGCCCUCACGCCCAUCCUCACGCGCUCCCGCGUGCUCAACGAGGAGCCCCUGACGCUGGCGGGUGAGGAGAUCGUGGCCCAGGGCAAGCGCUCGGACCCGCGGAGCCUGCUGUGCUAUGGCGGCGCCCCAGGGCCUGGCUGCCACUUCUCCAUCCCCUAGGCUUUCAGCAGGGCCCCGGCCAACCUCAGUGAUGUGGUGCAGCUCAUCUUUCUGGUGGACUCCAAUCCCUUUCCCUUUGGCUAUAUCAGCAACUACACCGUCUCCACCAAGGUGGCCUCGAUGGCGUUCCAGACACAGGCCGGCGCCCAGAUCCCCAUCGAGCGGCUGGCCUCAGAGCGCGUCACCGUGAAGGUGCCCAACAACUCGGACUGGGCUGCCCGGGGCCACCGCAGCUCCGCCAACUCCGUUGUGGUCCAGCCCCAGGCCUCCGUCGGUGCUGUGGUCACCCUGGACAGCAGCAACCCUGCGGCCGUGCUGCAUCUGCAGCUCAACUAUACGCUGCUGGACGGCCGCUACCUGUCUGAGGAACCCGAGCCCUACCUGGCAGUCUACCUGCACUCGGAGCCCCGGCCCAAUGAGCGCAACUGCUCGGCUAGCAGGAGGAUCCGCCCAGAGUCCCUCCAGGGUGCCGACCACCGGCCCUACACCUUCUUCAUUUCCCCGGGGACCAGAGACCCAGUGGGGAGUUACCGUCUGAACCUCUCCAGCCACUUCCGCUGGUCGGCGCUGGAGGUGUCCGUGGGCUUGUACACGUCCCUGUGCCAGUACUUCAGCGAGGAGGACGUGGUGUGGCGGACAGAGGGGCUGCUGCCCCUGGAGGAGACCUCGCCCCGCCAGGCCGUCUGCCUCACCCGCCACCUCACCGCCUUCGGCACCAGCCUCUUCGUGCCCCCAAGCCAUAUCCGCUUUGUGUUUCCUGAGCCAACAGCGGAUGUAAACUACAUCGUCAUGCUGACAUGUGCUGUGUGCCUGGUGACCUACAUGGUCAUGGCCGCCAUCCUGCACAAGCUGGACCAGUUGGAUGCCAGCCGGGGCCGCGCCAUCCCCUUCUGUGGGCAGCGGGGCCGCUUCAAGUACGAGAUCCUCGUCAAGACAGGCUGGGGCCGGGGCUCAGGUACCACGGCCCACGUGGGCAUCAUGCUGUAUGGGGUGGACAGCCGGAGCGGCCACCGGCACCUGGACGGCGACAGAGCCUUCCACCGCAACAGUCUGGACAUCUUCCAGAUCGCCACCCCGCACAGCCUGGGUAGCGUGUGGAAGAUCCGAGUGUGGCACGACAACAAAGGGCUCAGCCCUGCCCGGUUCCUGCAGCACAUCAUCGUCAGGGACCUGCAGACGGCACGCAGCACCUUCUUCCUGGUCAAUGACUGGCUUUCGGUGGAGACGGAGGCCAACGGGGGCCUGGUGGAGAAGGAGGUGCUGGCCGCGAGUCACGCAGCCCUGUUGCGCUUCCGGCGCCUGCUGGUGGCUGAGCUGCAGCGUGGCUUCUUUGACAAGCACAUCUGGCUCUCCAUAUGGGACCGGCCGCCUCGUAGCUAUUUCACUCACAUCCAGAGGGCCACCUGCUGCGUUCUCCUCAUCUGUCUCUUCCUGGGCGCCAACGCCGUGUGGUACGGGGCUGUUGGAGACUCUGCCUACAGCACGGGGCGUGUGUCCAGGCUGAACCCGCUGAGCGUCGACACAGUCGCUGUUGGCCUGGUGUCCAGCGUGGUUGUCUAUCCCGUCUACCUGGCCAUCCUCUUUCUCUUCCGGAUGUCCCGGAGCAAGGUGGCUGGGAGCCCGAGCCCCACACCUGCCGGGCAGCAGGUGCUGGACGUCGACAGCUGCCUGGACUCAUCCGUGCUGGACAGCUCCUUCCUCACGUUCUGAGGCCUCCACGCUGAGCAGGCCUUUGCUGGACAGAUGAAGAGUGACUUGUUUCUGGAUGAUUCUAAGAGUCUGGUGUGCUGGCCCUCCAGCGAGGGAACGCCCAGUUAGCCGGACCUGCUCAGUGACCCGUCCAUUGUGGGUAGCAAUCUGCGGCUGGCCAAGGGUGAAACCAACCUUUUCCUGCUGUGCGUGAUGGAGGAGAUCGAGCCACUGCACGAUGUCAACGCUAGAGAGCAG